GCAUCUAGAUCAAGUGGCGGCAGCACAGGCAGCUGGAAGGUACCCACAGAAAGAAAUCGAGCACUAUGUUCAGAAAGAUCCACUCCAUCUUUAACUCCAGCCCACAGAGAAAGACGGCGGCCGAGAGCCCCUUCUACGAAGGAGCCAGCCCCGCAGUGAAGCUGAUUCGAAGCAGUUCCAUGUAUGUGGUCGGGGACCACGGGGAGAAAUUCAGCGAGUCCUUAAAGAAGUACAAAAGCACCAGUAGCAUGGACACCAGCCUGUACUACCUGCGGCAGGAGGAGGACCGGGCGUGGAUGUAUUCGCGCACCCAGGACUGCCUGCAGUACCUGCAGGAGCUGCUGGCCUUGCGCAAAAAAUAUCUCAGCAGCUUCAGUGAUCUGAAGCCCCACCGCACCCAGGGGAUUUCCUCAACCUCCUCCAAAUCCUCCAAGGGAGGGAAAAAGACUCCUGUCCGGUCUACUCCCAAAGAAAUAAAGAAAGCAACCCCAAAGAAAUACUCGCAGUUCAGUGCUGAUGUGGCCGAGGCCAUUGCCUUCUUUGACUCCAUCAUUGCAGAGCUGGAUACAGAGAGACGACCCCGGGCUGCUGAGGCCAGCCUGCCAAAUGAAGAUGUGGACUUUGACGUGGCCACCAGCUCCAGGGAGCACAGCUUGCAUUCUAACUGGAUCCUGCGGGCACCGCGCAGACACUCCGAGGAUAUCGCUGCCCACACUGUGCAUACUGUAGACGGCCAGUUUCGAAGGAGCACCGAGCACAGGACCGUGGGCACUCAGAGGAGACUCGAGAGGCACCCCAUUUAUUUGCCCAAGGCUGUGGAAGGGGCCUUCAACACCUGGAAAUUUAAGCCCAAAGCCUGCAAAAAAGACCUGGGGAGCUCCAGACAGAUCCUUUUCAACUUCUCAGGAGAAGAUAUGGAGUGGGAUGCAGAGCUCUUUGCGUUGGAGCCCCAGUUGUCUCCUGGGGAGGACUACUAUGAGACAGAGAACCCCAAAGGACAGUGGCUGCUUCGAGAAAGACUUUGGGAGCGGACGGUGCCCUGACUCCAUCUGGAUUCCUUGACGUGUCUCAGACUGGGUCCCUGAGAAGCUGUCCGCUUUCAGCGCAGCAUGAGGUAUUUGGUAGAGUUGAAAAUGCCAAUUGUAACACAGUCAACCCACUCAGCACACUGCCUGCUGGUGCCGUGCCAGUGCCAAACAGACCUGUGGCUUCCCAGGGGACAGGUCUCAGGACACUCUCAGAGCUUGAGUUUCUCUGCGUGGGCUGAUGACCAGGGACUUACAGCCUGGCUGGUCUUCAAGAGCUGAAGGAAUGGAAGGUCUUGAGUGGAGUGUCUGGGCUCACUCCCCUGACCUCACCUGGCCUGGUCCUCAUUCUCCACGUGUCUGUCCAGGUGGCUGCUAGCAAUGUGCUCAGUACCAGAAAUGAACUCACCUGUAGAUUUCUGGGCCAAAGCUUCAAAGAGGUAGCUCCUCUUUCUAUGAGGCUCAGAGACAUGCUGGAUCUGCACUGAGGUUGCCGUCUUGUGUGCAGAAUGCAGUUGAGAAAGCAGCUCCUUUUGCUCUCUUUUCAGAGUUUUCCAGAAACUCCUGCUGCAUUAAGCUAAGAUGAGGCUAAUGCCCUGGCAAUGGGGUGAGGGAAGGGGUAUGUCACGAGCCUGCCUGGGGGCCACACUGUUUCCUCAGGCCCCAAAACUCAGCUCCCCUUCACAUAGGCAAUUGACAAGAGAAGAAGGGAGAUGGGGUGAUUCUUUUCUUUUUCUUCUAAUUCUUACCCAGAAAAAUCUUUUUAAAUAUCCAUGGAACCAGUUUAUGACAGGCCACACCUUUCCCUUUCCCCAGUUAAGAGAACAAUCAGAAUCAUUACGUUCUUUUGGUAUAGAAAGGAUUUCUGUAUUUUAGGAACUAUCUGAAUCAGAAUUACAUUUAAAAUAUAUUCUUUGUAUUUCUAAAUACUUUUUACAUUUUUGCAAUAGUUGUACCCAUUCAAGCUUGAGAACCACUGGUUUGGAGAAUAUACUGAAAUUUAUCUAUUCUCACUUCUUUUUUUGGCAUUUUCUUGUAAACCAGUCUGUGCAUGUAUAAGGGUCUUUGGGCAGAAGGAAGGGAGAGAGACAAAAAACAGAAAACAAAACAAAACAAAGAAAACCACAAUCAUUUGAAUUAAGCCAAGGAUGUUCUAGGCUAAGGUCAGGCUAAGAACUGAACAGAGGCUUCCUUUCUGCCAUGCCUGUGGGAUGAUAUUCUUAUUGUUCCAUUUUUUAGGAAGAACCUUUUGUUUAUGUGAACCUGAUCAUAUGAAUCUAAGAAUAUGUAACUCUUACAAAUAAAAAACAGCUAGUAAUUAUAUUGCAUUCUUAGAAAUUUUAUCUCAACAUGUUUUCAGAAUGAAACCAUACUAGAAAUGUUUUAAUACCUCUCUUUAUUAUUUUUCGAGUGCCAAUGUCAAUGUUUGGAAAGUUUCUUUCAUUUUGUUGCUUGUACUAACCCAGCUAUAGCCAGAAGCUUGACUGGAAAGUAAAUGUUUAGGAGAUUUGUUUUAUAAACUGCAUUAAAGCACUGCCAUUUAUCACCACAGAUCUUUUAUUUUCCCUAAAUGUGGCCUUGUUUGAAGCCUCAUCUAUAAAAGUUCAUUGUUGGGGAUAAACUCAGGAUAAAGGUGUCUUUACUCUGCCUCUUAUCAAACUACAGUUUAUCAUAGAUCCACCCUGAAAUUAUGUGGUGAAGAUACUGUGUACAUUUUGUUUUUAAAGAUAAGAAAAAAUAAACAUGACUGCGAGGAUGUUUGGAGUCCUGAUUUUUUAAAAAGCAUUUAUUGCUUAUGGCACAUGAAGCUGUGCCGUCUUAUUUUGCUUUGUUUUGUAUGUUUUUUGUCUUUCAUGAGACUAUACACAGCCUGAAAAAUUCCAUGAUUGGGAAACAGAAGGUUGUCUUGUCUUUGGGGAUCAUUUUUAGGUGUUUGAAGUUGGUGAUAAACCCAAGGAUCUGUGCUCUGCCUGGGGAAUCUUGAGAUGGUGUCUGGUGGGGUUUGAGAUAAAUGAAAUCUGAAACAAUAAAAGUCAAUUCAGAAAACCCA